AAAGUAACAACAGCCAGUGGAGACAAAAAGAACUGCUUCUCUUUCUUUCCCCCUCCAAGUUCCUAGUGGAGGGCUGAGUCCAGCAUCCCAGACUCGUGUGACUAUAUAGGCAAGCAUUUGGGGACCUACUUCACUUUGAUACCCUAGCCUUCAGCAGCUCAAGGUGUUGGCCUUUGGAUAGGAGGCUUCCAAGUAGUAAAGCUCCCUGCUCUCAGCAAGCCCAACACCAUGGGGAAGGGAGAUGUCUUAGAGGCAGCACCAACCACCACAGCCUACCAUUCCCUCAUGGAUGAAUAUGGUUAUGAGGUGGGCAAGGCCAUUGGCCAUGGCUCCUAUGGGUCGGUAUAUGAGGCUUUCUACACAAAGCAGAAGGUUAUGGUGGCAGUCAAGAUCAUCUCAAAGAAGAAGGCCUCUGAUGACUAUCUUAACAAGUUCCUGCCCCGUGAAAUACAGGUAAUGAAAGUCUUGCGGCACAAGUACCUCAUCAACUUCUAUCGGGCCAUUGAGAGCACAUCUCGAGUAUACAUCAUUCUGGAACUGGCUCAGGGUGGUGAUGUCCUUGAAUGGAUCCAGCGCUACGGGGCCUGCUCUGAGCCCCUUGCUGGCAAGUGGUUCUCCCAGCUGACCCUGGGCAUUGCCUACCUGCACAGCAAGAGCAUCGUGCACCGCCUGAUGCCCAGCCUUUCUGCUGCUGGUAGGGACUUAAAGUUGGAGAACCUGUUGCUGGACAAGUGGGAGAAUGUGAAGAUAUCAGACUUUGGCUUUGCCAAGAUGGUGCCUUCUAACCAGCCUGUGGGUUGUAGCCCUUCUUACCGCCAAGUGAACUGCUUUUCCCACCUCAGCCAGACUUACUGUGGCAGCUUUGCUUACGCUUGCCCAGAGAUCUUACGAGGCUUGCCCUACAACCCUUUCCUGUCUGACACCUGGAGCAUGGGCGUCAUCCUUUACACUCUAGUGGUCGCCCAUCUGCCCUUUGAUGACACCAAUCUCAAAAAGCUGCUAAGAGAGACUCAGAAGGAGGUCACUUUCCCAGCUAACCAUACCAUCUCCCAGGAGUGCAAGGUCCAACUGCUCAUUGCCUGUGUGGCACAAUGGAGAAAAACUCAGGCAAGACCUCUCUCUCCCCUGCUCUAGAACCUGAUCCUCCAGAUGCUACGCCAAGCCACUAAGCGUGCCACCAUUCUGGACAUCAUCAAGGAUUCCUGGGUGCUCAAGUUCCAGCCUGAGCAACCCACCCAUGAGAUCAGGCUGCUUGAGGCCAUGUGCCAGCUCCACAACACCACUAAACAGCACCAAUCCUUGCAAAUUACGACCUGAAAAUGGCUGAGGGAGGGGGCUAAGAGAGGAGCAAAGCAGGAGGUCUUGGGCUAAAAAUCUUUUUUACCAAAAAUAAAUCUAAGUCUGAUUUAGUUUCAUCAA